GAAGGAGCAGAGCGGCCGGAAGCGCGGAGGGAGCCGCGGGAUGGACCGCAGGGCUGCGGCGAAACCACGUGCUGCCUGAACCCCACUUUCCUCUUGCAGCCUGCCAGUUUUCUCCAUUCAAGAUAGUCCCUUUGGAGAUGCGCCCCUGGGUCGAAGCCACUACUGGCCAUCCCAGAGCCAGACCUGGUGUCCCAAGACCCUGAGCCCAUCCAGGUCUCAGAGAUCCAGGCUCCCACAAGCUCCCAAGGCUCUAGCCACAGGUCCCAACUCCCCUGAGCUGUUUGAGGAGUCCUGGCCAUCCAGUUCAGGGACCCCCUCCCUGCCCAGCACCACUGAGGGACAGAUGUGGGCCUCCCCAGCACCCACCCUGAUUGACAGCGGGGACUCCGUGGUGGCCAAGUAUAUAAACAGGUUCCGCCAGGCUCAGCCCACCAGUCGAGAGGAGCGCCAGCCUGCAGGCCCAACCCCAGCUGACUUUUGGUGGCUGCAGUCUGACUCUCCAGACCCCAGCAGUCAAAGUGCAGCAGGAGCCAACAAACCAGAAGGAAGACCCCAUACAGCUGUCCCUACUGCGGUCAACGUGACCAGUGCAUCCCAUGCUGUGGCUCCCCUUCAGGAAAUAAAGCAGAACCUCCACACAUGGAACUCAUCCCUGCUGGACCUGGAGACGCUGAGCCUACAGAGCAGAGCUGCCAGGCUGCUCAAACGCAGCAAAGCCUCCAUCUCCUCCUCCUCCUCCCUCAGCCCCAGCGAUGCCAGCACUUCCUCAUUCCCCACCAGCUCUGAUGGCCUCUCUCCCUUCUCGGAGACCUUCAUCCCUGACUCCAGCAAGGGCCUUGGCCCCAGGGCACCCGCAUCCCCGGCACCAGCCCAGGCCCAGACCCCCACCCCUGCUCCAGCCCCAGCCUCCUCCCAAGCACCCCUUCGGCCAGAGGAUGACAUUCUGUACCAGUGGCGGCAGCGGCGGAAGCUUGAACAGGCUCAGGGAAGCAAGGGUGACAGAGCUUGGGUGCCGCCUCUGACCCCUGCCCUCCGCACGUUGACCUCUCCUGCUCCAGUGGAGACCCUCAGUUCUCUGGGGACCCAGCCUAACCAUGUCCCACUGUGGAGCAGUGUGGCCCAGCCUGGUCCACCAGAGGCCUUCUAUGUGGAGAGGCCUCCUUUUCCCUCAGUGUCCUCUCCACACAUCUUUUGGGCCCCCAGCUCCCACGGGUUCUUCUGGGCCCCACAGUCUGGGCCUUGGGUAUCCCUUGGGGCUGUUCCUCCCACGCAGCAGGCCUCCACCCUAGCACAUCUGGGCUCUACCCUCGCGCCCCCGGCUUCCCUGGCCUCCACCCUCGAACCCCCGGCCUCCACCCCAGCUCCCCUGGCCUCCACCCUUGCACCCCCAGCCUCCACCCCGGCUCCCCUGGCCUGUACCCCUGCACCUCCAGCCUCCACCCUCGCAUCCCCAGCUGUCCCCCAGGGCCUGCCCAUCCCUGACCCAAGCAGCUGUGCCCAGCCUAAGAGCCUGGGGCCCAAGUCUCGGAGGAGCAGAGCCCCUCGCCCAGAGGCUGCCGAGCAAGUCCCUGCAGCUGGCCAGGGACCUGGCCCUCAGCUCAGGGGUGUCCUGGGCCAGGUAGUGGCAGCUCGGCUGUUCCCUGACAGCCUGGAGGACACGCCUCCUCACUUCGAGGGCCCCCCUCCACCCAAGGCUGGAUCUCCGAAAGUCCAGGCCACACAACCCCAAACCAAGGUCACUCCCCCUCCAUCUGAAUCCCAGUGUCGGGCCAAGGCCGAGUCUCUGAAAGCCAAGGCCUUGCCGCCCGCAGCGGGGUCAGUGAUACGGAAGAGCGAAGCCACUCCUUCCCCUGGAGCCUGCCUGCAGCCCGAGGUCCCACUCUCUCCAGCUGAGCAGGCAACCACAGUCAAGGCCUCGCCGCCAGCCUUCCAGGUGGGGUCUCCGGAGGCCCUGGCCCCGCCCCCGCCCGCUGCUGACCACGCCCCCUCGGAGGCCCUGCUUGCCCAGGCCGCCCUGCUGCUGCAGGCUGCAGAAGACUCCGACGGCAGCGAGUUCCAGGACGAUCCCGUGCUGCAGGUGCUAAGAGCCCAUAGGGCAGAGCUGAGUCGGCAGAAAAGGGAAGCGGAUGCCCGAUUAUCGUUCCUGUUGGACCAGGCUGAAGACCUGGGAUCUUGGUCCCCUCCAGCCGGGUCGCCCCCUAGGUCCCCAAGGAGGCUGCUAAGAAGGGAAGGAGAUUCCCUGGAGGCCAGAAGACUUUGAAUUGUACAGAUUCUAUUUUACCCAGUGAGGCUCUUUUUUUUUUUUUCAUACAGUUACUGGUUAUCUGUGAGAAAGGGGUUGUUUGGAAAGGCCAAGGGGUCAUGCCAAUUUAAGGAAAUGCCCCCCAUCCUCCGCUGCCCCAUGGCUCUGCCCUGCCCCCCACCCCUUCCUGACCACGGAAACAAGAUCUCCUUUCUGGUUAUAUCUUCCUUGGGGCAGAGGGAGUUUCAGACAAGACUUCUGGCAAGACUGGGACCCACCUUAUCUGGCUUCACUCAGGAGCCCUGGCUCAAAUGGACCAAAGGACUGCCCUCCACGGAGGAAGCUACUAGGGUCAUCAGAGUGUUGGAUGAUGGUCAGGCUAUAGCCCACACAUGCUUGAGCAGCAGCAGCAUCUGGUGCAGCUGACCCCUCCCUCCUUGAAGCACUUUCUCUCCCUGCUUCCAGCCCUUCUCUCUGCACCUCUCUGGUCAGGCCUAGUCACUAGCCCAGCAUGUCAACUUUGGCAUGACCCAGGGCCAUGGCGUUGACAUCUCUAUCUGCACCCACCCAUAGGUGCUCUUGUCUAGCUUAAUGACUCUAAACCCCGUCUCUAUUCUGAUAAUCCUCAAAUUUCUGUCUGUAACCUAGACCUGGCCACGAAACCUUGGGCUCCUACCUCAUUACCAUUUCUACCCAAGGGUUUAAAAGACAUCUCAAAUUCCAUAGGUCCUAAAUGGAGUUUCCAAUCUUUCCCCCUAGGCGUGCCUCUCCCCAGCUUCUUUUUUUUUUUUUUUUUGGAUGGAGUCUAGCUCUGUCACCCAGGCUGGAGUGCCAUAGUGUGAUCUCGGCUCACUGCAAGCUUCGCCUCCCGGGUUCACGCCAUUCUCCUGCCUCAGCCUCCCGAGUAGCUGGGACUACAGGUGCCCGCCACCACGGUCGGCUAAUUUUUUUUGUAUUUUUAGUAGAGACGGGGUUUCACUGUGUUAGCCAGGAUGGUCUUGGUCUCCUGACCUCGUGAUCCACCCGCCUCGGCCUCCCAAAGUGCUGGGAUUGCAGGCGUGAGCCACCGUGCUGGGCCCCCCCUCCCCAACUUUCUUCGGCUCUGUCCUUUGCCGCUCAGACCAAAAACCUUAGAGUUGUCUUUGACUUCUGUCUUUCCCUUCCACCCACAGUUAACCAGGAAAUCCUGCCAUCUCCGCCUUUAUUUUAUUUUAUUUUUUGAGAUGGAGUUUCACCCUUGUUGCCCAGGCUGUAGUACAAUGGCAUGAUCUCGGCUCACGGCAACCUCCACCUCCCGGGUUCAAGCGAUUCUCCUGCCUCAGCCUUCUGAGUAGCUGGGAUUACAGGCACCUGCCACCACGCCCAGCUAAUUUUCUUUGUUUGUUUGUUUGUUUUGAGACAGAGUCUUGCUCUGUCCCCCAGGCUGGAGGGCAGUGGCACGAUCUCGGCUCACUGCAACCUCUGCCUUGCAGGUUCAAGCUAUUCUUCUGCCUCAGCCUCCCUAGUAGCUGGGACUACAGGCGUGUGCCACCACGCCUGGCUAAUUUUUGUAUUUUUAGUAGAGACGGGGUUUCACCAUAUUGGCCAGGCUGGUCUCAAACUCAUGACCUCGUGAUCCUCCUGCCUCAGCCUCCCAAAGCGCUGGGAUUACAGGCAUGAGCCAUCAUGCCUGGCAAUUUUUUGUAUUUUUAGUAGAGACGAGGUUUCACCAUGUUGGCCAGGCUGGUCUCGAACUCCUAACCUCAGGUGUCCCACCCACCUCAGCCUCCCAAAGUGCUAGGAUUACAGAUGUGAGCCACCGCACCUGGCCUCCACCUUUAAAAUCUAUCCAGAAUUCAACUGCUUCUCCCCUUCUACUGCUCACACCUCAAUCUAGGCUGUCAUCACCUCCUCUCUGGACUGUUGGAAAACUUAACGGUUUUUAUAAACCUGAUAUUCUUUGACACACUUGCCAUCAAGAGGCAGAGUCUAUGUCCCUUCAUCUUGAAACUGGGCCCCUCAACAAAUAAAAUGCAGAGGAAGUGAUGCAGCUUAACUUCUAAAGUGCAGUUAGAAAAGAUGAUUUCUCAGCUGGGCAUGGUGGCUCACGCCUGUAAUCCCAGCACUUUGGGAGGCUCAGGUGGGCAGAUUACUUGAGGUCAGGGGUUCAAGACCAGCCUGGCCAACAUGGUGAAAUGUCUCUACUAAAAAUACAAAAAUUGGCCAGGCAUUGGUGGUGGGUGCCUGUAAUCCCAGCUACUCAGGAGGCUGAGGCAAGAGAAUUGCUUGAACUCAGAAGGCAGAGGUUGCAGUGGAAAAAAAAAAAAAGAUAAUUUCUCUCUCUUUCUCUCUCUCUCUGACACUUGCUUUAGAGGCUACAUUAAAAAAAAAAACUAGUUGCCAUGCUGGGGAGGGGUUUGGGUUACACAGGUGUAUGCACUUAUGAAACUUAGUGAAGUGUGUGAAUUUCAUUGUAUGUAAAGUUUACCUCAAAAGAAAAUAUUGAACGCCAGUUAAAGAUACGCCUGUAAUCUGACUUCUUUGGGAGGCCAAGGCGGGAGGAUCACUUGAGGCCAGGAGUUUGAGACUACCCUGGGCAACACAGCAAGACCUGUCUCUACAAAAAUAAAUAAGUAAAUAAAUAGCCAGAUGUGGUGGCA